AGUCCUUGCAACCCGGUGCACUGGCGAGGCCCCUCCUGCGCGUGCGUGACUGAGGCCUGGCUUUCCAGGGAUCUCCCACCUCUUCCCUCUCAGCCCUGCGCAGCCUCCUUCCGUCUGUAACUCACCUAAAGACCCAAGACCUGCGACAUCCGUAGACCGCGCCCGCUAUGCACAGCUAAAGAGCACUCACCCCUCGCGCACCAGUCCCGGCCCGGCAGCCGCUGCCCCGGGCUCGACUGGGCGCUGCUACCGCCAUCAGCAAGAGCAGGAGCAGCCGGGUUGCCCCAGCGCUGGCUGCCGCCAUCUCGGCUUCUUCCCACCAGCGAAGGGACGGCUGUGAGCCAAGAGCCGCGGAGCACGCCGGGAGGAACAGGCCGCAUCCUGACGCCCGUGCGCCUGCGCUGGGCCCCGGCACCUGCGCACUGGCACCCGUCCGCACCUGGGGCCUGACGUCAGCAGGAUGGGGCCGCCCCUUUGGCCUGAUCUCCAGGAGCCGCCCCCUCCAGGGACGUCAUCACAAAUCAGGAGCCCGCUCUUGUGUGACGUCAUAAAGCCCGCUCCGCAUCAUGACGUCACAGUGCGCGUAGUCCCGCCCCCUCGCUUUCUCCCUCUGCUCCUCCGUCCGCUCCCGUCGGACGGGGACAUUGCAAUGAGGCGGGAUCGCGGCCCUAAGCCGGCCCUGGGUGGAGCUGGCGAGGUGGAACCAGGUGGGAUGGCAGCCUCUCCCACGGGCCGUCCCAGACGGCUCCAACGCUACCUCCAGAGCGGCGAAUUCGACCAGUUUCGGGACUUCCCCAUCUUUGAGAGCAACUUCGUACAGUUCUGCCCCGACAUCUAUCCUGCCCCGACCUCUGACCUCUGGCCCCAGGUGACUCGGUUGGGAGAAGUUGCCAACGAGGUCACCAUGGGGGUGGCAGCCUCCAGUCCAGCCCUGGAGCUCCCGGACCUAUUGCUUCUGGCCGGCCCUGCCAAGGAGAACGGACACCUGCAACUCUUCGGGCUGUUCCCCUUGAAGUUCGUCCAGCUCUUUGUCCACGACAAAAGCCGGUGUCAGCUCGAGGUCAAGUUGAACACCAGCCGCACCUUCUACUUGCAGCUGCGGGCCCCACUCAAGACCCGAGACCGAGAGUUCGGCCAGUGGGUGCGGCUGCUCUACCGCCUGCGCUUCCUCUCUGCUUCUGCUGUGCCCUUCACGCAGGAGUAAGAGCCCCAAGGCGUGGAAGCCAGACUUGACCCCAAGACCUCUGAACUCUGGGGACUCUGAGUCUUCCAGCAUCCUUCAAGGUCACCGAAUGACCAGAGAUCAAAGUACCUUGCCUCAGGGCCGGGCAGAUGAGAUAUUAAAGUUAAUAAAGGUCAGUCCAUUAAGAACCAA